ACCUGGCUCCGCGGGCAGCCGGAGCGCACCCGGCCGGAAGCCGCUGUCGGGGAGCCGGCGGUGGGGCUGGACGCAGGUGCAACUGACAUGGGUGAACCCCAGGGAUCCAUGCGGAUUCUAGUGACAGGGGGCUCUGGGCUGGUAGGCAAAGCCAUCCAGAAGGUGGUAGCAGAUGGAGCUGGACUUCCUGGAGAGGACUGGGUGUUUGUCUCCUCUAAAGACGCCGAUCUCACGUGGCUGGCCUGGCCUGGGUGUGCUUGGCUGUGUUCCUGGAAAAACAAACACCCUCCCAUCUCUUCCUGGAAGCCUGCACCCUCAUAUCAGCCAGGCCCUGGGGCCACCCUCCCUUUUGACUGUCCCUCCUGCCAUAGUCCCACCCAGUUCCUGCACUUGGCACCCAACCCUGGGGUGCUGGUUCCCUCCAGAGCCUCCUGACAGCCUGGCUUCCUACAGGGAUACAGCACAGACCCGCGCCCUGUUUGAGAAGGUCCAACCCACACACGUCAUCCAUCUUGCUGCAAUGGUGGGGGGCCUGUUCCGGAAUAUCAAAUACAAUUUGGACUUCUGGAGGAAAAACGUGCACAUGAACGACAACGUCCUGCACUCGGCCUUUGAGGUGGGCGCCCGCAAGGUGGUGUCCUGCCUGUCCACCUGUAUCUUCCCUGACAAGACGACCUACCCGAUAGAUGAGACCAUGAUCCACAAUGGGCCUCCCCACAACAGCAAUUUUGGGUACUCGUAUGCCAAGAGGAUGAUCGACGUGCAGAACAGGGCCUACUUCCAGCAGUACGGCUGCACCUUCACCGCUGUCAUCCCCACCAACGUCUUCGGGCCCCACGACAACUUCAACAUCGAGGAUGGCCACGUGCUGCCUGGCCUCAUCCACAAGGUGCACCUGGCCAAGAGCAGCGGCUCGGCCCUGACGGUGUGGGGUACAGGGAAUCCGCGGAGGCAGUUCAUAUACUCGCUGGACCUGGCCCAGCUCUUUAUCUGGGUCCUGCGGGAGUACAAUGAAGUGGAGCCCAUCAUCCUCUCCGUGGGCGAGGAAGAUGAGGUCUCCAUCAAGGAGGCAGCCGAGGCGGUGGUGGAGGCCAUGGACUUCCAUGGGGAAGUCACCUUUGAUACAACCAAGUCGGAUGGGCAGUUUAAGAAGACAGCCAGUAACAGCAAGCUGAGGACCUACCUGCCCGACUUCCGGUUCACACCCUUCAAGCAGGCGGUGAAGGAGACCUGUGCUUGGUUCACUGACAACUACGAGCAGGCCCGGAAGUGAAGCUGGAAGACAGGAUCAGGUGCCAGCGGACCAUCGGCUGGCAGAGCCCAGCGGCCACCACCCGUCAACCCUGCCAGGAGCUGAGGGCACCACCCAGCAACCUGGGCCUGCAUUCCAUCCGCUCUGCAGCCCCAAGCAUCUUUCCAGUGGGGCCCCCAUUCACGUUGGUCCUCAGGGAAACCAGGGUCCCGGGCAGGCCCGGCGCUUUGCUCCCCACACCAGCCCCCUGCGCGUGUCCACUCUGAUCCUGCAUCCCACUCCCUGGGAGCCAAUAAAGUGCAUUUUCACAGGC